AGUGAGGAGACUCGGCCAUGCUACGCGCGCUGAGCCGCCUGGGCGCGGGGACCCCGUGCAGGCCCCGGGCCCCUCUGGUGCUGCCAGCGCGCGGCCGCAAGACCCGCCACGACCCGCUGGCCAAAUCCAAGAUCGAGCGAGUGAACAUGCCGCCCGCGGUGGACCCUGCGGAGUUCUUCGUGCUGAUGGAGCGUUACCAGCACUACCGCCAGACCGUGCGCGCCCUCAGGAUGGAGUUCGUGUCCGAGGUGCAGAGGAAGGUGCACGAGGCCCGAGCCGGGGUUCUGGCGGAGCGCAAGGCCCUGAAGGACGCCGCCGAGCACCGCGAGCUGAUGGCCUGGAACCAGGCGGAGAACCGGCGGCUGCACGAGCUGCGGAUAGCGAGGCUGCGGCAGGAGGAGCGGGAGCAGGAGCAGCGGCAGGCGUUGGAGCAGGCCCGCAAGGCCGAAGAGGUGCAGGCCUGGGCGCAGCGCAAGGAGCGGGAAGUGCUGCAGCUGCAGGUGGGCAACGUCUCCGGAGGGUGGGACUCCAGCCGGGGACGCGGCUUGCGGGGCACUGGGAAUUCUGGGCACCGCGACGCGGGCGCUGGCUAUGUGCAGAGACUUACAGUUGGCAGGUCCGGAUUUGGAGAGGAGAGUGCCAGUCAGGCGCAAAGACCCGGAGGAAGAGGUGAAAAACUUCAUCACCCGAGAGAACCUGGAGGCACGGGUGGAAGCAGCAUUGGACUCCCGGAAGAACUACAACUGGGCCAUCACCAGAGAGGGGCUGGUGGUCAGGCCACAACGCAGGGACUCCUAGGGGCCCAGUAAGGACAGUGCCCGCCAGGGACCAUGUAUGUAUCAUGGCGGAAGAGUUGGCCCUGACCUGGAAUAAAGCAGUUGGUGUUGCUUAUGAGGAAGGUUCAGCCUUAUCCAGCACAGCCUUCACGUUUUGCCCUCUGCUGUCACCACUUGGUCAGAAACUUCCAAACGCAGUGCCCUGUUCUGCCGGUGUGUACAGCCUCAGCGCACCAGGAGACCCUAGAGUGGUUUCCAUCUCACAGAGAAUCAGACAGGGCCACAGCCCCCUCAGGCAGCCAGGUCAUCUGAGUAUCAUUAAGAGUAGUGAUGGGAAGAUUACAGUCUGAGGGCCAAACGUGCCUGCUUCCUGUUUUUGUAAAUAAAGUUUUGUUGGAACACA